CCAUAUGGGAUACCUAUUUAGUCAGAGCCACUUUCUAAUUUUUCUUAUGUGUAAAAAUUUUAGAAAAAUAUCAUUUAUUGAUUUUUAAUUACAAAAGCUGUAAUAGAAGUAUAUAAGUUAAAAAUGGAAAUCUCUCACCCAACCUCUUUCUCCAGAGGUAAUUACUGUUAAUAGCUUGGUGUAUAGUCUUUCAUUUUUAUAUACUUACUGACUUUUUUUAUACAGAUGAUAUCACACUAGGCGUGCUCUUCUGGAAUUUGCUUUUCUUCAUGUAACAAUAUAUCUUGGGGCCGUUUUCAUAUGAUUACAUAUCGACUUGCCUUGUUCUUUGUCAUGGUGGAAUACAUUCCAUUGUUUUUAAAGCAUCAUGAUGUAUUUUGUUGAUUCUUUACUGAUAAUUAUUUAAGGUGCUUUUUAUCUGAGGAGGAGAAGAACUUUAAGAGAUUUUUGAGGAUGUCAUUUAAGAAAAUUCCUUAUCUAUGUUUUUCAUGACGAUGACAAACAUUUGCAAAGUACUCCUCAUAUAUAACCUCACUUCACACUCCUAACAACCCUGUAAUGACGUUACCAUUAUCCAUAAAUAACAGAGAAACAGAUGAGACCAGGGAGCCCCAAGGCAGGGAUCACAUGUGCCUUUGCUGUUAUAAUGGUAGCUAGGUACCCCUUUUCCCCUUCCACAUGACAUAGGAAAACAUAUCCUUUUUGUCCUUGGUGACAAAAGGUCACCAAGAGUUAGUUACAACUACCUAAUGGGAGACUUCAUUUCUUUCAUCUCUUGUGGUUGUUCUAAAUAGUUUAUUGGCCCAUGAUAGAUAUCAACUUCCUUACUCUAGGCAAUGCUAUAUUUCUAUCUCCAAUAAAUUCUUUGUAGGUCAUCUUAUUCUGCCACCAUUUUUGAAUUUAUAAAUUCAUGAGAAAAAAAGUUGCCUAAGGGCAAAAGAGGAUUUAUUUAAUAAAAAUCUUUGACCCAGCAAUAAUCAGUAUCCAUCCUGCUGAUUCAUGCAGCAUUGAAAUAGUAUGCCUUUUACUGCCUCCAAGAACAUAUUUUUGGUUGUUGAUAUUUUAAAAUAAAUAUGACAUCAGAUUCAGUCCAUCAACAUAUAUUGAGGUUUUAUUGUAUAGAAAGCACUUUAAAUAUAUCAUUUAUGAUCCUUGAAGAUACAUAGAUGAGAAAACUGAGUCUCUGAGAGCUUAAGUGCCCAAAAUUGAGUGAGAAGGUGAACAAAAAUUCUCACCCACAUCAAACACUCUUAAAUACACAACUUGGCUAUGCAGGCAAGUUACCAAUGUAUCAAAGCAACUUGUGAGUCAUUGACAAGCAGAAUCAUUGCUGAAGUCCCUUCUAGUUCUAAAACUGUGCAAAUAUUUAGGAGCAGUUUUGUUGGUUUGGACAUGAUGGCUUCUCACUUUACCCCAAACUCAGAUUCUGGUAUCAUGACAUCUCAUAGAACUAGGAACCAUUUUGCACACAAAAAGAGAUCACAGUCUUUUUUCCUCUGGUUGUUUAUUCAAAAUAAACUAGCCAACAUAAGCAAGGUAAGACUUUAAUUUUGAUUUUCAGAGAAAAAGACAACAACUCUUUGAUAAUCCCCAGUAUCACAACCUUCAAAAAUAGCGGAGGAGAGUGGGGUAGAAAUGAGGUAGAGAAAAGAGUAAAAGAAGUGGGAUUCGCUCUUGAUGUUAAGUCAGUACAUCUCACAUUACCUCCUGAAGAAGAACUAGAGAAAGUGUCAUCUUUGUUGUAUAAAAAGAAAUAUGGCAUAAUGAUCCAGCAAUCCCACUACACUUUGGGUGUAUAUCCAAAGGAAGCAAAAUCAGUAUUUUGAAGAGACAAUUGCAUACUCAUGUUUAUUGUAACAUUAUUCACAAUAGCCAAGACAUAGAAUCAACCUGUAUGCCCAUCAGUGGAUGAAUGGAUGAAGAAAAUGUAGUAUAUAUGUACAGUGGAAUACUAUUCAGCCAUAAAAAGGAUGAAAUCCUGUUCUGUGUGACAAUAUGGGUGAACCUGGAGGACAUUAUGUUAAGUGAAAUAAGCCAGGCACAGAAAGACAAAUACUGCGUGAUCUCACUCAUAUGUGGGAGCUAAAAAAGUUGAGAUCAUGGAAGUUGAGCAUAGAGUAAUGAUUACUAGAGACUGGGGAAAAUAGAAGGAAGCAGGAGAUGAGGAAAGUUGAUUAACAGGUACAAUGUUACAGUUAGAUAGAAGGAAUAAGUUCUGGCACUCCAUUGUACAGUACCAUGACUAUAUCUAACAAUAAUGCAUUGUAUAUUUCAAAUAGCUAGAAGAGAGAAUUUUGAAUGUCCUCAUAACAAAGAAAUAAUAAAUGUUUAAGGUGAUGGAUAUGCCAAUUACUAUGCUUUGAUCACACAAUGUAUACAUGUAUCAGAAUAUCACAUUGUAUCCCAUAAAUAUGUAUAAUUAUUAUGUGUCAGCAAAAAAUAAAUAAGGCAUAAAGUUUAUUCAGUUAAUAUUUAUGGAAUCCCUACUACAUGUCAGGCACUGUGCUAAAUCCUGGGGAUAAAAUGAUGAAUUUGCUUACAGUCUUUCUCUGAAGGAACUCACAGUCUAAUAGUAGAGAGAUACAAGAUUAAAGACUGUAAUAUGGUAUUGCAGUGAUGGAAAUGUGAACAGGAUAUUCAGGAGCUCAGAGGAGGAGCAGGUCAAGCUGGCUUCUUUAAGGAAGGUGAUACUUAAAGUGAGCCUUUAGCAAUGAAUAAAGUUAGCCAGCUUAAGAGAAGUGGGAUAGAAAGAACAUUCCAGGUAAGAGCAGAAACACAGAGGUCAUGGUAGUUAAAGCACAGAGUUUGAAGAAAGGAGAGAAGAGAGACGAAUGUUGGGAACAAGCCCCCCAAAAUCUGGCCGUAAACUGGCCCCAAAACUGGCCAUAAACAAAAUCUCUGCAGCACUGUGACAUGUUCAUCAUGGCCAUAACGCCCAUGCUGGAAGGUGGUGGGCUUUCCAGAAUGAGGGCAGGGAACAUCUGGCCCGCCCAGGGCAGAAAACCGCUUAAAGGCAUUCUUAGGCCACAAACAAUAGCAUGAGUGAUCUGUGCCUUAAGGACAUGCUCCUGCUGCAGUUAACUAGCCCAACUUAUUCCUUUAAUUCGGCCCAUCCCUUCGUUUCCCAUAAGGGAUACUUUUAGUUAAUCGAAUAUAUACAGAAACAAUGCUAAUGACUGGCUUGCUGGUAAUAAAUACGUGGGUAAAUCUCUGUUCAGGGCUCUCAGCUCUGAAGGCUGUGAGACACCUGAUUUCCCACUUCGCACCUCUAUAUUUCUGUGUGUGUGUCUUUAAUUCCUCUAGCACCGCUGGGUUAGGGUCUCCCUGACUGAGCUGGUCUCGGCAGACGAGGCUUUUGGGGAAGAUUUGUUGUUGUUGUUGUUGUUUUAGGCAGAGUCUUGCUCUGUCGCCCAGGCUGGAGUGCAGUGGUUACACAUCUUGGCUCACUGCAACCUCUGCCUCCCAGGUUCAAGCCAUUCUCCUGCCUCAGCCUCCCAAGUAGCUGGGAUUACAAGUGUGCACCACCACACCCAGCUAAUUCUUUUGUAUUUUUAGGAGAGAUGAGGUUUCACCAUGUUGGCCAGGCUGGUCUCAAGUGAUCAGCCCACCUUGGCCUCCCAAAGUGCUGGGAUUACAGACAUGAGCCACUGCACAUGGCCUGGAAGAUGGGUUCUGUUUGGAGUCUGAGACACCCCAAUCAAAGUGUUUAGCAGGGAGCUGAAUAUGUGGGGCUGAAGUUUAGGGAUCAUCUGGGAUGGAGACAGAGAUCUAAGAGGUAGGAAGUGAUAGCUGAAAAUGUGAGAGUUAAUUAAACCAGCCAGGGAGCAUAUACCACGUGAGAUCAACAGAUAUUUGAGACUAGAAUGCAAAUAAAAAUCAACAUAUAAGGGACAGACAGAGGAAAAUGAGCUCAAGAAGCAGAGACAGUAAGUAGUCAGGAAGAUGGGAGUAAACAUAAGAGUUUAGUAUCACAGAAGCUCAAGGUGUAGAAUUGAAAUAAAGGUGUGGCCUGGCCAGGCGCAGUGGCUCACGCCUGUAAUCCCAGCACUUUGGGAGGCCGAGGCAAGCGGAUCACAAGGUCAGGAGAUAGAGACCAUCCUGGCUAACACAGCGAAACCCCGUCUCUACUAAAAAUGCAAAAACAAAAUUAACCGGGAGGCUGAGGGGGUGAGAAUGGCGUGAACCCAGGAGGCGGAGCUCGCAGGGAGCCAAGAUUGUGCCACUGCACUACUCCAGCCUGGGUGACAGAGAAAGACUCUGUCUCAAAAAAGAAAGAAAGAAAGAAAGAAAGGUGUGGCCUAUGGAGACAGAUGGCCUUGCUGUUCUGGCAAGGUAAGGACUGAAAAGAUGAAGACAUUAGAGGCAUCAGGAAAGGCUUUGAUCAAUAGUGAGGAUGAAAAAGGUGAUUUUGAGAGGAAGUAAAGAGAAAACUGUAGUCUACCCUUGAGAUAAAUCUGGAUGAGAAGACAAGAGAGGUUGGGUGACAGUUAGAGGAAUAUAGGAGGUCAAGGGAGGAGGAGGUGGCGGAUGAAUUGCUUUGAGAAUGCAAAAUAAGAGAUUUCAGUAUGUUUCUAGACUGAAAGGAAAAGGCAGUGGAAAGGUUGAAAACGGGAGACCUAGGGAAUGACAAAUGGAGGGAACUCUCAGGGGAGGAACAUCUUGUGCACUUAGACUGGAGAGGUGGAGAGGAUACUCUCACAUGAUUCAUAGACAAUUUGGCCCACCCGAUUUAAUACUCUGCCUGCAUCUCCUAUUACAGAUUCUCUCUUCAUUUUGUCAGCAAACAGCUCACUGUCCUCUGGAUCUGCUGCGUCCUGCAGGAGCAUUGCGCUUAAACUAUGGGAAGCGGCACCUCCACCCAACAUCAUUUUGCUUUCCAGAAUGCAGAGAGAGCCUUCAAGGCAGCAGCCCUGAUCCAGAGAUGGUACCGGCGCUACGUGGCCCGCCUGGAGAUGAGGCGGCGUUGCACCUGGAGCAUCUUCCAGUCUAUAGAAUAUGCUGGGCAGCAAGACCAAGUCAAGCUCCAUGACUUCUUCAGCUAUCUCAUGGAUCACUUCAUCCCCAGCAGCCACAACGACAGGGACUUCCUGACCCGCAUAUUCACUGAGGACAGAUUCGCCCAGGACUCCGAGAUGAAGAAAUGCAGUGACUAUGAAUCCAUAGAGGUACCCGACAGUUACACGGGGCCACGCCUCUCCUUCCCACUCCUGCCUGACCAUGCAACUGCCCUGGUAGAAGCAUUCAGACUGAAACAACAGCUCCAUGCUCGCUACGUCUUGAACCUUUUGUAUGAAACCAAGAAACAUCUGGUACAGCUGCCAAACAUCAACCGGGUCUCAACCUGUUACAGUGAGGAGAUCACAGUGUGUGGAGACUUACAUGGCCAAUUGGAUGACUUAAUCUUUAUAUUUUAUAAGAAUGGCCUCCCGUCGCCAGAACGGUCAUAUGUGUUCAACGGUGACUUUGUGGAUCGAGGCAAGGAUUCAGUAGAGAUCCUGAUGAUUCUUUUUGCCUUCAUGCUGGUUUACCCCAAAGAGUUCCAUCUUAACAGAGGAAACCAUGAGGACCAUAUGGUGAACUUACGAUAUGGCUUCACCAAGGAAGUGAUGAAUAAAUACAAGGUACACGGGAAGGAAAUACUAAGAACCCUGCAAGAUGUUUUCUGUUGGCUUCCACUGGCCACUCUGAUAGAUGAGAAAGUUCUAAUUCUUCAUGGUGGGGUGUCAGACAUAACUGAUCUGGAGCUUUUGGACAAAAUAGAGAGGAGCAAGAUAGUUUCCACCAUGAGGUGCAAAACGAGACAGAAGAGUGAGAAGCAGAUGGAGGAGAAGAGAAGAGCCAACCAGAAGAGCUCUGCACAGGGACCCAUCCCAUGGUUUCUCCCCGAAAGCCGCUCUCUUCCCUCUUCGCCCCUUCGGCUUGGCUCCUACAAGGCCCAGAAAACCAGCAGGUCCUCCAGCAUCCCCUGCAGCGGUUCCCUGGACGGGCGGGAGCUCUCCCGGCAGGUGCGGAGCUCCGUGGAACUGGAGCUAGAGCGGUGCCGGCAGCAAGCAGGCCUCCUGGUGACCGGAGAGAAAGAGGAGCCCUCCCGCUCAGCCUCAGAAGCAGACUCUGAAGCCGGAGAGCUGCGGAAGCCCACUCAGGAGGAGUGGAGGCAGGUUGUAGAUAUCCUGUGGAGUGAUCCCAUGGCUCAAGAGGGCUGCAAGGCCAACACUAUUCGAGGAGGAGGCUGUUAUUUUGGGCCUGAUGUGACACAACAGUUGCUACAAAAAUACAACAUGCAAUUCCUGAUCCGUUCACAUGAAUGCAAACCUGAAGGCUAUGAAUUCUGUCACAACCGCAAGGUAUUAACAAUCUUUUCUGCCUCCAACUACUAUGAAGUUGGCAGCAACAGAGGGGCCUAUGUCAAACUGGGGCCAGCCCUGACCCCACAUAUUGUGCAGUAUCAAGCUAACAAGGUGACCCACACACUCACCAUGAGGCAAAGGAUUAGCAGAGUGGAGGAGUCGGCUCUGAGAGCUCUGAGGGAGAAGCUGUUUGCUCAUUCUUCAGAUCUUCUCAGUGAAUUUAAGAAGCAUGAUGCAGAUAAAGUCGGUUUAAUCACCUUGAGUGACUGGGCAGCAGCGGUGGAGUCUGUGUUGCACCUAGGACUGCCAUGGCGGAUGCUGAGGCCACAGCUGGUGAACAGCUCAGCAGACAACAUGCUGGAGUACAAGUCUUGGCUGAAGAACUUGGCCAAGGAACAACUGAGUCGCGAGAACAUACAAUCAAGUUUGCUGGAAACAUUGUAUCGAAACCGAUCCAACCUAGAGACCAUUUUUAGGAUCAUAGACAGUGAUCAUUCAGGGUUCAUCUCACUGGACGAGUUCAGGCAGACCUGGAAGCUGUUCAGCUCUCACAUGAAUAUCGACAUUACAGAUGACUGCAUCUGUGACCUUGCUCGGAGCAUUGAUUUCAACAAAGAUGGCCACAUUGAUAUCAAUGAGUUCCUGGAGGCCUUCCGCCUUGUGGAGAAAUCCUGCCCAGAGGGCGAUGCCUCAGAAUGCCCACAAGCUACAAAUGCUAAAGACAGUGGCUGCAGCAGUCCAGGUGCACACUAAGAACAGCCUGGUCUUCAUCACCCAAAGUGCCUCAUAGGCAAUGCUCAGCUUCUCACUAGACUAUCUCCCUUAUUCUCCAUGUGAAACUUUAUGCUGAAAAUUUACCUAUCCAUAUGCAUCAGAAUCACCUGUGUAUUUCAGUGUGGAGGGGUGGGUUGGGGUGUUGUGUAUGUAUGUGUUUUAAGUAUAUGAGUGCCCCAACCCCACCUCACAAUCUUCACAAAGUAGAACUUAGGUAUAGUGUUUUCAAAUUCUAAAGUCCACUUCAGUUAAGAACCACUGACAAUGUAA